ACUCCCACCUCCAGAGUCCAAGGGUCUAUGUGGUGGGCAGUUUGAGCUGGCUGGAUACUAGAGGGAGGCUGCACCUGAAGCAUUUGGUGGGUGAGCAGCAUGGGCUUUGAGGAGCUGCUGGAGCAGGUGGGCGGCUUUGGGCCCUUCCAACUGCGGAAUGUGGCACUGCUGGCCCUGCCCCGAGUGCUGCUACCACUGCACUUCCUCCUGCCCAUCUUCCUGGCUGCCGUGCCUGCCCACCGAUGUGCCCUGCCGGGUGCCCCUGCCAACUUCAGCCAUCAGGAUGUGUGGCUGGAGGCCCAUCUUCCCCGGGAGCCUGAUGGCACGCUCAGCUCCUGCCUCCGCUUUGCCUAUCCCCAGGCUCUCCCCAACACCACGUUGGGGGAAGAAAGGCAGAGCCGUGGGGAGCUGGAGGAUGAACCUGCCACAGUGCCCUGCUCUCAGGGCUGGGAGUACGACCACUCAGAAUUCUCCUCUACCAUUGCAACUGAGUCCCAGGUCGGUAUUUACAUAAUCCAUCUGGAGGUGGAAUGUCGGUGGAGGCAGUCUCCCUGGGAGGCAGCAGGUCGAGGCCUUCCUUGGGAAGAAGCUGAGGCUGCAGGACUGGGGAGGGACAAAGUUUCCUAUUCCCCAAGCUGGCGUGAAUCGUUGGGAGGUUUAUUAUCUGGCAUGGAGUGGGAUCUGGUGUGUGAGCAGAAAGGUCUGAACAGAGCUGCGUCCACUUUCUUCUUCGCCGGUGUGCUGGUGGGGGCUGUGGCCUUUGGAUAUCUGUCCGACAGGUUUGGGCGGCGGCGUCUGCUGCUGGUAGCCUACGUGAGUACCCUGGUGCUGGGCCUGGCAUCUGCAGCCUCCGUCAGCUAUGUAAUGUUUGCCAUCACCCGCACCCUUACUGGCUCAGCCCUGGCUGGUUUUACCAUCAUCGUGAUGCCACUGGGUGAGGCAGAGCUGGAGUGGCUGGAUGUGGAGCACCGCACCGUGGCUGGAGUCCUGAGCAGCACCUUCUGGACAGGGGGCGUGAUGCUGCUGGCACUGGUUGGGUACCUGAUACGGGACUGGCGAUGGCUUCUGCUAGCUGUCACCCUGCCUUGUGCCCCAGGCAUCCUCAGCCUCUGGUGGGUGCCUGAGUCUGCACGCUGGCUUCUGACCCAAGGCCAUGUGAAAGAGGCCCACAGGUACUUGCUCCACUGUGCCAGGCUCAAUGGGCGGCCAGUGUGUGAGGACAGCUUCAGCCAGGAGGCUGUGAGCAAAGUGGCCGCCGGGGAACGGGUGGUCCGAAGACCUUCAUACCUAGACCUGUUCCGCACACCACGGCUCCGACACAUCUCACUGUGCUGCGUGGUGGUGUGGUUCGGAGUGAACUUCUCCUAUUACGGCCUGAGUCUGGAUGUGUCGGGGCUGGGGCUGAACGUGUACCAGACACAGCUGUUGUUCGGGGCUGUGGAACUGCCCUCCAAGCUGCUGGUCUACUUGUCGGUGCGCUACGCAGGACGCCGCCUCACGCAAGCCGGGACACUGCUGGGCACGGCCCUGGCGUUCGGCACUAGACUGCUAGUGUCCUCCGAUAUGAAGUCCUGGAGCACUGUCCUGGCAGUGAUGGGGAAAGCUUUUUCUGAAGCUGCCUUCACCACUGCCUACCUGUUCACUUCAGAGUUGUACCCUACGGUGCUCAGACAGACAGGGAUGGGGCUGACUGCACUGGUGGGCCGGCUGGGGGGCUCUUUGGCCCCACUGGCGGCCUUGCUGGAUGGAGUGUGGCUGUCACUGCCCAAGCUUACUUAUGGGGGGAUCGCCCUGCUGGCUGCCGGCACCGCCCUCCUGCUGCCAGAGACGAGGCAGGCACAGCUGCCAGAGACCAUCCAGGACGUGGAGAGAAAGAGUGCCCCAACCAGUCUUCAGGAGGAAGAGAUGCCCAUGAAGCAGGUCCAGAACUAAGUGGGAGUGGAGGCAGGCCCUCCACAGAAGCUCUGCAGCAGGGGCUGGGAGAGCAGAAGGGCAGGCCCUGCAACUCAGGCUGGGAGUAUCGAACCCUCUGCCUAGGGCCGGAGUUGCUGCCAGUACCCGCUCCCUCUGCUCAUCCAUCCUUGAUUAUUUGGCUUCUAGGAACAGUUGACUUCCCAGAAUGCAGUGGGCUGCUGGGCACCCCUCUCACGGUUGGGGAGGAUUCUGUAAAUAAAGGUGCCCCUUGGGUUGGGGCAGUGGUGACGAGCUGUGGGAAGAGCCCUGGAUAGGAAGCCACUGAGUCUGCCCUGGGCUCUGAUAAAACCUUCACCAUUAACUUGCUGUGUGACCUUGGGCAUGUGGCUUUCCCUCUCUGGGCCUCAGUCUGUUCAUCUCCCAAAUGGAUAAUGAAGCCUCUUGGGAGGCCCUACCAUAGGAUCUGUUGCCAUGCUCAAAUGAGUUACUGAAUAAGGUGCUUCUGCUUCUUCUAGAGAUGGUGCUAAAGAAAGGACUAGCAUAUGAGACUUCUGGUACCAAUGGGGCUGGUGGGCAUGCUGUCCACUGUGUGGUGCUAGGACUGCCAAUGCCAGGCCCAAGGGACAAAAAGAACAGAGCUUUUUGUUCUCAUGGCUGGCCCUGCUACCUCCGAGGCACCCUGCAGGGCAAUGCAUGUCAUCCCAACCCCCACACUCCCCAUCCUCCAACCCACUGGUCUCAUGCCCAAAGAAGAGUUGAAGGCAUGGGAGCCAACAUUUUAUUGAAGAAGCCACAGAGGCUGAAAUUCAAUAAACACAAGUUUUAUGAGUA